AGUCCGUUGAGGCUGCCAGGCGAGUCAGGUCUCUCUGGACCUCGCCUGACUCGGCUGGGCUGUGCCUGAAAUUGACCCAGCUCCACCAUACUCCUUGAUUAUGAGAAAACAAGGAGUAAGCUCAAAGCGGCUGCAAUCUUCCGGCCGCAGCCAGUCUAAGGGGCGGCGCGGGGCCUCCCUCGCCCGGGAGCCGGAGGUAGAGGAGGAGAUGGAAAAGUCGGCCCUAGGCGGCGGGAAACUGCCAAGGGGCUCCUGGAGGUCCUCCCCGGGGAGGAUCCAAAGUCUGAAAGAGCGAAAAGGCUUGGAGCUAGAGGUGGUGGCCAAGACCUUUCUUCUCGGCCCCUUCCAGUUCGUCCGUAAUUCCCUGGCGCAGCUCCGGGAAAAGGUGCAGGAACUGCAGGCGCGGCGGUUCUCCAGCAGAACCACUCUCGGCAUCGCUGUCUUUGUGGCAAUUUUACAUUGGUUACAUUUAGUAACACUUUUUGAAAAUGAUCGUCAUUUCUCUCACCUCUCAUCUUUGGAACGGGAGAUGACUUUUCGCACUGAAAUGGGACUUUAUUAUUCAUACUUCAAGACCAUUAUUGAAGCACCUUCGUUUUUGGAAGGACUGUGGAUGAUUAUGAAUGACAGGCUUACUGAAUAUCCUCUUAUAAUUAAUGCAAUAAAACGCUUCCAUCUUUAUCCAGAGGUAAUCAUAGCCUCCUGGUAUUGCACAUUCAUGGGAAUAAUGAAUUUAUUUGGACUAGAAACUAAGACCUGCUGGAAUGUCACCAGAAUAGAACCUCUUAAUGAAGUUCAAAGCUGUGAAGGAUUGGGAGAUCCUGCUUGCUUUUAUGUUGGUGUAAUCUUUAUUUUAAAUGGACUAAUGAUGGGAUUGUUCUUCAUGUAUGGAGCAUACCUGAGUGGGACUCAACUGGGAGGUCUUAUUACAGUACUGUGCUUCUUUUUCAACCAUGGAGAGGCCACCCGUGUGAUGUGGACACCACCUCUCCGUGAAAGUUUUUCCUAUCCUUUCCUUGUACUUCAGAUGUGUAUUUUAACUUUGAUUCUCAGGACCUCAAGCAAUGAUAGAAGGCCCUUCAUUGCACUCUGUCUUUCCAAUGUUGCUUUUAUGCUUCCCUGGCAAUUUGCUCAGUUUAUACUUUUUACACAGAUAGCAUCAUUAUUUCCCAUGUAUGUUGUGGGAUACAUUGAACCAAGCAAAUUUCAGAAGAUCAUUUAUAUGAACAUGAUUUCAGUUACCCUUAGUUUCAUUUUGAUGUUUGGAAAUUCAAUGUACUUAUCUUCUUAUUAUUCUUCAUCUUUGUUAAUGACGUGGGCAAUAAUUCUAAAGAGAAAUGAAAUUCAAAAACUGGGAGUAUCUAAACUCAACUUUUGGCUAAUUCAAGGUAGUGCCUGGUGGUGUGGAACAAUCAUUUUGAAAUUUCUGACAUCUAAAAUCUUAGGCGUUUCAGACCACAUUCGCCUGAGUGAUCUUAUAGCAGCCAGAAUCUUAAGGUAUACAGAUUUUGAUACUUUAAUAUAUACCUGUGCUCCCGAAUUUGACUUCAUGGAAAAAGCGACUCCGCUGAGAUACACAAAGACAUUAUUGCUUCCAGUUGUUAUGGUGAUUACAUGUUUUAUCUUUAAAAAGACUGUUCGUGAUAUUUCAUAUGUUUUAGCUACAAACAUUUAUCUAAGAGUCUUGCUCUGUCAGCCAGGCUGGAGUGCAGUGGCAUGAUCUCUGCUCACUGCAGCCUGGACAUCCCGGACUCACGCGAUCAUCUCAUCUCAGCUCUGCCAGUCAGCUGGGACUACAGGUGUGCAUCACCAUGCCCAGCUAAUUUUUGUAUUUUUUUGUAGAGAGGGGGUUUCACCGUGUUGGUCAGGCUUUUCUUUUUCUUUCUUUUUUAACUUUCAGAGGGGGUAUAAUUAUUUGUGUUCCUGAAUAUUUAUGAAUUUUCUUCUAAACUUAUUGUUAAAACUAUUUAUUGUAUAACAUUUUUGGAUGGUUUUAGUAAUGUCACUAGCAUAAGCAGAUGCCAGCAAAAUGUAUCGUAUCAGUCACACAUAAGUAAAUUGCUACAAAACUCAAGAAGUAAAUUGUGAAGAAAAUUUCCUUCUGAGGGAAAUAUGAUCUCAAAUGACAUGUUUUUUAGUGUUCAACUUUUAUUUUCGAUGCAGGGGGCACAUGUACAGUCUUGUUAUAUGGGUAUAUUGUAUCCAGGUGGUGAGCAUAGUACCUAAUAGUAAUUUUCAAGUUACAUUUUAUAUUUGUAAAUAGAAUAUUUGAUUUUAUUUUGUGACUUCUACUUUAUAGAAUAGUUUUAGAUUUAUAGAAAAAUUGUGAAGACAGUAGAAAGAAUUUCUAUGAACUCCAUACUCCAUGCUUGUAUUUUUAAUAAACAGCUGUGUAUGGUUGUCAGAAGAGCUAAUUAAGCUCUUAGGUGCAUCUGUUGAAAUUGUUUCCAAAAUAAAGGGGAUAAUAGAACCAUUCUAUAUUGUUCCAGACAGAUGGAGCACAGGGAAAUGUGUCUUGGCAUUCUAAAAAAGAAUGAAUGGAGAACCCUGGACACUGUUCCCAUAAGGAGUACAUGAAGGGACUUGGGAUAUUUAAUUGGAUAAUAGAAGAUUGAAGGGUAUGUGGCAACUGUCUUCAUAUAUUGCAGAGGGUGUAAUGUGGAAGCGACAGACUCGGAGGGGUCAAUGGAUGGAAGAUAAUUACUCAGAAUAUGGAAGUCUAUGUAUUGAUUACAUAUUUGAAAGUGACAGGCCUGUUGUGUAUGGGCAGAGGGUUCCGGGUUAAAUCUCAAAAAUAAUAAUAGCAGGGGCUAGUAGUAAUACAUUCUGAAAAACCAGCGUAUCAAAAAGAGAGGGAAUACUCCCCUCUCUUAGAUCUGCUCCCCUGGGUGCUGAUUGUAAGUAGCUUUGUAUGUUUUAUUUUAGAAAAUACAUAUAGAAACACAAUAUUUUAAAAAAAUAGAAUUGUAUUCUUCUUAUUCUGCAACUUGUUACUUGUAUUUAAUAGUGUGUCUUGGGCCUCUUCCUUGAUCUUCAUUAUAUUUUAUAAUGGUCUUAGGAUUUUAUUGUUGACCAUCAUGCGUGACUGCCUUUCCCAUAUCAAUGAAAGUUUAGAUUAUAUAUAACUUUUGUCUUAAAAAAACCAAUGUUUUGAGGAUUGAACAUCCUGGUUCGUGUAUCUUGGUACACUUAUUCUAAGUAUUUCUAUAGUAUGAAAUAUUUGAAUUUGGACUGCUGAUUAUGAGGCCUGCAUAUUUUAGAAUUUGUUAAAACUGAGAAAUUAUAAUGAUGAGAGUGUCCAUUUCUCUGCAACUCCACCAACAUCGUUAUCAAGCUUUUAAUUUUUUCUGAUAGGUAAAAACAAUUCAUUUUAUUGUAUCAAUUCUUUGUCAGUGGAGUUUUGCAGCUUUUCAUGUGUUUGUUUACUAUGUUUCUUUUUGACCUUUAAAAGUUGUUUUGUGGGUUUUUGUUGUUGUUGUUGUUGUUUUGUUUUGUUUUGUUUUUUUUGUCUCGCUGCUGUGUAUGCAGUGGCACAAUCUCGGCUCACUGCAACCUCUGCCUCCGGGGUUCAAGCAAUUCUCCUGCCCCAGCCUCUGGAGUAGCUGGGAUAACAGGCACCCGUCAUCACACUCAGCUAAUUUUUAUAUUUUUAGUAGAGACAGGGUUUGCCAUGUUGGCCAGGCUGGUCUCGAACUCCUGAACUCAAGUGAUCCAGCCACCUGGGCCUGCCAAAGUGCUGGGAUUGCAGGCAUGAGCCACUGUGCCCGGCUAUGUGUUAUGUUUUUGCUUUUUCCAUAGACGUAACAUUUUGUCUCUUAUGUGCAUUACAUAGUUUCUUCCAAGAUGUCAACUUAUAGUUCAUUUAUGGUCUCUGCUUUGUAGAACUUCAAAAUUUCUCUACAAUCACAGUUAUAUAUUUUUUCUGGGUUCAUAUGUUGCUUAGAACACUUCCCUAUACGAAAAACAUGAAAAUUUUUUUUCAUAUUUUCUUUCAUAAGUGUCUAUUUACAUAUAGGUUAUUUAUUACUCUUGCGUUAAUUUUGUGGUAUAGUGACAUAGAGGAGUCUACCUUUCCCCCUCUAAUGAGGUAUUGUCCCAACACAGUGUUGCAUAAAUCUUUUUUCCAAAUGUCAGCUUUUAUCACUUAUCAAUUCUCAUUGUACUUGAGUCUGUUUUAGAUUGUCUCUUAUAUUGAUCUUUUAGUUUAUAGGAAAGCUGCUUUACUUUUUUUUUUUUUUUUUUUUUUUUUUUUUUUUUUUGCAACACAUUUUUAUCUAGCCACAUUACCAAACUUUCUUUCUGGUUCUGAUAGUUUUUCCAUUGAUGUCUGGAUUUUCUAGGCAGGUUAUCAUAUAAUCUACAAAUAGUAAUAACUUUCUAAUAUUUAUACUUCUUUACUUUCUUGUCGUGCUAGAACUUCCAGAACAAUUUUGAAUUGCAGUGAUGAUGGGCUUGCCCUUAUUUUGUUUCUGACUCUAAAGUGAAGAAUGCCUUUAGUGUCUCACUGUUUCAUUUACUGUUAGUAUAUAAUAGAUAGCCUUUAUUUCAUUAAGAAAGUUUCCUUGGCCAGGCGCGGUGGCUCACGCCUGUAAUACCAGCAUUUUGGGAGGCCAAGGUGGGCGGAUCACGAGGUCAGGAGAUUGAGGCCAUCCUGGCUAACAUGGUGAAACCCCGUCUCUACUAAAAAUACAAAAAAUUAGCUGGGCAUCGUGGUGGGCGCCUGUAGUCCCAGCUACUCGGUAGGCUGAGGCAGGAGAAUGGCGUGAACCCGGGAGGCGGAGGUUUCAGUGAGCUGAGAUCGCGCCACCGCACUCCAGCCUGGGCGACAGAGUGAGACUCCGUCUCAAAAAACAAAAAAAAAAAAAAAAAAAGAAAGUUUCCUUUUGGUUUAUAUAAACCAGGAUAAUUUUAAAAAUUAAAUUAAAGAUAGAUGUUGAAAGUAUAUAAUGUGUGAAUUGUAACUCAAUAAAGCAGUAAAAAAUGAAUGUUAAAUUUUUUAAAAAUGGCUUUAAAAAUAUUUUGGGGAUUAUUAUAUAUUUUUUCUCCUUAUUAAUAACUACACUUGUUUUUAAAAUUUGGUAAGAAUGCUUAACAUGUGAUCUACCCUCUUAACGAUUUUUUAAUUGUAUAAUACAGUAUUGUGGACUAUAAGUAUAACAUUCUAUAGUCGAUCUCUCGAACUUAUUCAUCUGGCUUAACUGAAACUUUUAAAAUAUUCAGUAAAUCAUGCUGUGACAGAUGUGCUGUCAUCCAGGCUUUGUUGUUCCAUUUGUAGAGUAGAGGCAGAGUAGAUUUAGCAUAAUUCUGAAAAAAGGCCUCAGGAUUUUCAAAGUGGUAAAUGAACAUUGGCUUCAACCGAAAGUCACCAGCUGCAUUAGUCCAUAACGAGGUCAUUCUUUUUUGGAUUUUUCAUAAAACCAGCUUUUGGUUUUAUUCCUUAUAUUUAUGAAGGUUGUUCUCCAUUUUAUUAAUCUCUGUUUAUAUGUUUAUGUCCUUAGUUUUUCUUUUGGUGCACUUUUGUUGUUUUUCUGUGUCUAAAGUUCACAUCAUUUAUUAUCAAUCAUUAUUGUGUCCUAGUAAAUACAUUUAAAGUUAUAACUUUUUCUUUGAAGAAAACGCACACUGUAUCCCAUGAUGUGUGUAGCAUUACCAUUAAUGUUGAUUUCUGUGUAGUCUGUGAUUUGAGUUUUGAUCAUUUAAUCCAAAAUCACUUAGAAGAAUGUCUUAAAAUGUCUAACUAGUUUUAGGCCGGGUUCGGUGGCUCAUGCCUAUAAUCCCAGCACUUUGGGAGGCCAAGGCGGGCGGAUCACGAGGUCAGGAGAUCGAGACCAUCCUGGCCAACACGGUGAAACCCUGUCUCCACUAAAAAUACACAAAUUAGCUGGGUGUGGUGGCACACACCUGUAAUCGCAGCUACUCGGGAGGCUGAGGCAGGAGAAUCGCUGGAACCCAGGAGUUGGAGGUUGCAGUGAGCCAAGAUUGCCACUGCACUCCAGCCUGGCAACAGUGCGAGGCUCUGUCUCAAUAAUAAUAAUAAUAAUAAUAAUAAUAAUAAUAAUUUUUAAAAAUGUCUAACUAGUUUCUUCUGUUGUAUAUUUUGCCUUUAAAAUUAACUUGCUAUCUAUUGAGAUGGAUGUUCAGUUUUAGUAAAUGCUCUGUGAGGAUUUUUUAAAUGUUCAUUUCUUAUUUAGGGGAAGUUCAAAGUUACAUGUUAUAUCAUGUUAUUAAUAGUGCUAUUCCAAAUGGUCUAGUACAUCAACUUAUUUUUCUACUUUAUCUGUUUUCUUAGAAUGCUAUCUUCACAUACAACAUUAAAAAUGAAUUUUUCAAAA